CUCCCUUUCAUCAGUCUUCCCGCGUCCGCCGAUUCCUCCUCCUUGGUCGCCGCGUCCUUGGCUGGCGUGUGAGUACCGCGGCCCCCGCCGGAAGGAGUCGGGCGCGACAGAGACGCCCGAGGGGCCGGGAGGGCGGGCGGCCCGGGCUGCGCCAGAAGCUCGCGCCGUUAGGGACUGAGGCACAAGUGCGCCAGCGCGGGCUUAGGGGCCGUGGGCCAAGUGCGGCACUUGGGGCGAGCGCAGAGAGGCGGGGCGACGGAGGCCACGUGGCCGGCUUGGAGGGCGUCCGCGGGACGGGGGCGCCGGGAGCACUGUCUCACGGCGCAUCCCGGUCGUGGAAGCCCCUCGGCCAGGCUGCUGGGGCCUAAGGCCUGUGUUUGCUGCCGUCUCCGUGGGAGACCAGACAUCUGCCCCAGCUGUUUCUCUGGCCUGCAGACCUUCGUACACCACGUCUUUGUCAAGCACCAGUUACUGCACGCAUCAGCUGAGCACGGAGGGGAUAGGCACGGACGCAACACUUUUGGAACUUAGACGCUAGUGAGCACGGAAAGGAAUAAGCCUGUACUGUGACUGGGUCAAAAUUUCUGUCUCUUGAUUUGGAUAGGGUGGUCGGGCAGUCUCUGAAGGGGGCGGGGAUGCUGUUGCUAAGAAGUAGUACUUUCAGAGGCUUUAAGUGGAAGGAAGAAGGCAAAGGGGGCGGAGUGGGUUGGGGACCUGAUGAGACGUCAGGAUUGGUUUCCAGAAUGAAGGACCGCCUGGCAGCAGAAGAACUGUGUAGCUAAACUUGGGGUUGUCCCUGCCCGACAGGGCGGGGUGCUUCUUAAGUUGACACUGCCUGCGGCUCACCUCCCAGGGAGGCAGGCCAGGCCAUCUCACCUGAGCAGCCUCCUUCUACAGCUCCGCCCACCCCGUCAUCUGGACCCCAUGAGCCUUAAGCAGCUGGCUCGCAGGCAGUUGGUUACUUCCGGAGCCCGUGUGUGCCCAGCCCCGUUCUGGGGGUGGGGGAUGCAGCUGAGGGGCUGGGCAGGUGUGGAAGGAGCCCCCGAGCGUCCUCUGAGGAAGUAGACGCUCACCUUCGCCUUCUCACCACAUGCCUCAGGCCCAGCCAGGCUCCUAGACCUGCCUCUGUAGAGGCUUUCUGGGCGCAGUGCCAAUCCUGUGAGACAGCAGCAUCUCCCCUGGGCUGCUGCAGGGUUCACACGCAGUCAGUGCUGGCAGAGUGAGCGCCCAGCCGACAGAGCCCCCGCUGCCUCCCGCCUCCUCUGGAGGACUAGGCCCUCUGGGCUUUGCUCCCGGGUUGCUGGGUGAGGCUGCAAGGUUUAGCACAGGUGGGCACACGUGCUUGAUGAUGGACAAAGAGUACCUGGGCUGUGCCGUGCACUGGCGUCAGCCUUCUGGGGGCUGAGGACAGGAAAUGUGGCAUUGAGGAUUUGUGGGUCAUCAUCCUGUGCCAGUGUGUUAAGGUGACAUCAGCGUGUUGGAAGCUGGUGGCAGUGAGUUAUGCUAAGUGCUGGUGUAGGAGCCUGCCACAGGUCUCCAGCUCUCCCACCUCGCUGACAGCCAAGGGUGCCGUGUGAGGUGUGGCGUGGGUAUUGUCUGGGGUUCCAGAAAGCCUGUGCCGUGCUGGAGUCACCCAGGAGGCACAGGGGCUGCGCCGGGCAGGCAGGUCGGCCAGAGCCCCUCAAGCAGGGCUGGCCAUGGAGCUGGCCUGCAGUGGCAUUUAAGAAAAGACGUGGUUGGGGCGGGGCUUGGCCUGGGGCAGGGUGGGUUGGGUAGCUACAGUGAGUGCUCUGAGAUAUGCAGGACAGGCUGGCGUUUCCCAGUGGGGCUGGAAUAUCCAGGGGUCAGACAGGAAAGUGGCUGAGUGGGAAUGUGGAACUGUGGAGUUUUUUCUCUUAAAAAGACCAAAGGCGGCUGGGCGUGGUGGCUCAUGCUGGUGAUCCCAGCACUUUGGGAGGCCGAGGCAGGCAGAUCAUGAGGUCAGGAUAUCGAGACCAUCCUGGCCAACAUGGUGAAACCCCGUCUCUACUAAAAAUACGAAAAUUAGGCUGGGCGCAUGGCUCAUGUCUGUAAUCCCAGCACUGUGGGAGGCCAAGGCAGGCAGAUCACCUGAGGUCAGGAGUUCGAGACCAGCCUGGCAAACAUGGUGAAACCCCAUCUCUACUAAAAAUAUGAAAAAAUAGCCAGGUGUGGUGGCACACGCCUGUAAUCCCAGCUACUUGGGAGGCUGAGGUAGGAGAAUUGCUUGGACCCGGGAGGUGGAAGUUGCAGUGAGCUGAGAUCGUACCACUGCACUCCAGCCUGGUGACAGAGUGAGGCUCCGUCUCAAAAAAAACCCAAAAAUUAGCUGGCCGUGGUUGCGCAUGCCUGUAGUCCCAGCUACUUGGGAGGCUGAGGCAGGAGAAUCGCUUGAACCGGGGAGUUGGAGGUUGCAGUGAGCCAAGAUCGCGCCACUGCACUCCAGCCUGGGUGACAGAGUGAGACUCCGUCUCAAAAAAAGACCGAAGGCCUCACUCCACGCAGGAAGACAUUGAUCUGUCCUGUGGCUGCUCUGCCGUGCGGUGGUUUUGCCUAAAGACCCGCUUCCUCAGGGGCUCCAGCCUCUUUUAAGGGCUAGUCGUCGCGCCCUUUGGGCACUGAAGGUACUGAAAGUUCUAUCAGGCAGUGCCAGUCCACAGACUCAGGCCAGCCAGGUGGGCCGGAGAGGGGUGCUGCUGGGAGGGGUGGGCGUGCACAGGCUGAGCCGGUGGCUGACCCCGUCCCCUGCCCACCUCCCUGACUUCUCCCUGUGGAGGGUGGACAAUCUGGGAGCCUGUCUGUGUGUGCGACUGUGAUGGGGUGGCGUGGAGGGCAGGGCCUGGGAGCCAGCUCCUCCCAGAAAGCUUCCGUUUGCCCAGAUGUGUGGAGACCUCCAGGCCGUGCAGCACCUUGGUGGCCACAGCUCUCCAGGAUGUCCUCACCUUCCUCAGGGCCCUGCCCUCCUGACCUGGAGUGUUCUGGAAAGCUCCUCCUGAGCUUGGAUAAACUGCAGGAGCGAAGGGGCUGACCGUUUGUCGGGACGCAGUUGAAAGAGUCGCUGUGUCCUGCUCCGGGCUCUCCUGCUGGAGAGGAGAGGCUUGCACGUGCCUGUCGUCUGCGCAAGCUUUGAAGCUCAGACUUGGUCUCUGUUAGGAGAGAUGGUGCGCUGCGUCCGGCAGGUCCUCCCAUGCUUGGGAAUGCGGGAAGCGGGGAAAUGAGGAGGUGGGCUCGGACGUGUGGGGGGCUGUGCUGGCUGUCCUGGGAGGCUCUCUGCCCGCUGUUAGUGGCCAGCUCCCCAGGUGACGGGCCUGGCCUCCAGGUCUCCAGCAUGGCUUACUGUGGUGUCUCCUGAGGGCUUCCUCUCUGCAGGGAAGCCCACCCAAGAUCCCUCUUACUGGUCCCAUGGGGCAGCUGCCUCCGUAGCAUCCUCGUCUCCACCAGACCCCUGCAGGGUGCCCAGUUCCUCCCUGCAGGGUGCUCCCUGCUGCAGUGUGGGGUGCACAGAGGUGGGCAGGGCCCUGGGGCCGGAGCUCCCGUUGGUGAAGGAAGACGGAUCCCAGCCAGGGCUCUCGGGUUGAUCAGCAGUAGGAGGUGGCCCCUCCUGCCCAGUCCCACCCAGGACAUGGGCUGGUGGCUGGGCUUUCAGCUGUGCCCAGCUGCCCUUCGCAGAGCUUGCAGGGUUUAUGAGGUGGCUCUGGUGAGAUUAGGGGCAGGACACCUAGUGUCUCCAGCCGAGGAGUGAACUGGGUGGAGGUCCUGUCCUUGUGUGCACAUUGUGGGAGAGUCAGUCUGGGAGGCCUUUGUAGCUUGUGCUGGGGCCCUUGGGUGCCAGCCCUGUCUUGACGGUGGCUCCUGCUGAGAGAGAGGCCCUGUAUUAAUGUGAGCCCUGGGCUGCCUCCCCCUUGAGGGUCCUUGUCAUCUUCCGGGCCUCCUUCAGCAGACCGGACACAGGGGCAGUGCAGGUGAGGGGCUUGGGGGAGCUCCUUGGCAGCUCCAGGGGAUGCUUGUGGGCGCUGGCUUAUCUUGUCUCAGGCUACCUUGCUCAGGUGACGACAGGGUGGGUGGAUUUGGGAAAGGUUGGCUCAGAUAGUGGUCCCUGCUUGUCCCCCAGGGCCUGCCUAGGCUCCAACUGACAGUAAUCCCAAGAGCUCCCCUUUCAGGGGAUGACGGAGUGACGUCACCUGUGUGGACUCAGCUGCCACCUGGGAUUGUGGUGGCGGCGGGUCUGUCUGGCGCUCAGCUUCCAUCUCCACCAGUGUCACCUCCACACCACCUCGCCAAGCAGCUUCUGGAAAGGCCCCCGGCCGCCCCGGGCUGACCUGCUGCUGUGUCUGACCCGGUUAGUCUUUCUGGCUGCCUCUAACCUUGCUGCUUUUCCUUCAUGCUGUCCUAGGAGGCCAAAGCAAAGUAAGUACUCGCCUGUCCUCAUGCCCCAUUCCCCUUCAUUUGACCGGGGAACCCCCAGCCCUCGCUGCACCUGAGGGAACCCAGCACCACCUGCGCAUGGCCCAGUCUGCCCAGAGGGCCUCAGUUUCCCAUCUGGAAAGUGGAGGAAUUGGGUUUUCUGGAUGGGGCAGCAGCAGGUGGGCACCCUGUGUGGCCGUGAGCAGGGUCCUGUCCUGGGCUGGCGGGUCAGCAGCUGACAUGCGGCUCCCUGCAGGGAACAGGUGGCAGUGCCAGGUCUCGGUAGGAGCCUUGAAGUGGCUUCCCCUCCCUGAGCGGCGGCUUCUGCCCGGAGCCCCCAAGAACAUAGUCUGAGGCCACUUUGGCCAAUAAAGUCUGGUAGGGCAUCAACACUGGGGGCCAGCUCAGUGGCACUGCUGAUGGGACCUGCACGGCUCCAUGGGAGCAGAGAGACUGGUGGGGGUACCACCGCACGAUGUCACAAUGCCCUGUCUCCUGGGCUCUUGCUCCCACCCCACCCCCAACCCACAACCCCUGCCUCUGCCCAUCAGCCUGGCCUUGGUAAGUGCUGCCCCAGCCUGGGGAAGGAAUGAGCAGGGGAGCCUAGGGAGCGUCUUCAUGGGCCCUGUGGCCUCCCAUGGGCCCCGGUUCCUCGUUGGUGCCAUUAGAACUUGUUGCUGGGACUGCGGGAUUCGGGCCACAUGCCCGCAAAGAACUCCAUGUUCCACUUAGAGGCUGCAGAGUGCAGUGCCAGGGGUGCCUUCCCAAAAGUCCUCCCUGCCUGGGUGGAGCGUAGACAGCUCAGCACCCCACGGGGGGCGUUGGAGCCAGCCUUGGUUUUGUUGGGUAAGGAUGUUAGAAGAGGGGCGAAGACCCAUAGCCACUGGUGUGAAGGGUCUGCUCUUGACCGAAGGCUGCCUCCCUCUGGGUGCAGACCAGGCAGGUGGUCCCAGUCACGGUGCCCUGGGGCCACUGGGUCUGUCUGCCCUCAGGCUCCACUAGACACACCUGCGGAGGCAGCAGACUAGCAGCGGUGUCUGUGAGGGGCAGCUGCACAGCCCCCUCUUGAGGGUGCUCCUAGGCGUUGGUUAGGCCCAGGCGUUUCUGCUUUUGGGGAGCAGAGCCUGGAGUCGGGCAUGGCUGGGGAGGAAGCUAUCGCAGGCUGAGCGCGGGCUGGGGUGCUGACCUGCAUCCCAAGAGCAGAUUUGCCCCUGGCCUUCUGGGCCUGUCCUUUCUGUAACACCACACUGGACACCUGGGAGCAGAGCGUGCCCCCGGCAGGAUCCCACAUGGCUGCUGGAGCACUGGGGCAGCAGGUGACUGAGGUCGCCCAGAGCUUGAGGGAACACCUCAUCCAGGGAGGAGGCUGAGGCUCCCAGGCCACAGUAGCAAGUGGGGAGUGGAGCCUCACAACCUGCCUCCCACCAAGAUGGUCCCUCUUAACAUUACACAGAAGCAAAACCUUAGAGGGGGCCCUGAUGUCCUGGGACUGUGAGAGCCCCAUGAUUCCCCUUUAGCUUGGAUGGACCCAAAGGUAUGGACUCCAGCUGGGAGGCGGGGGCAGCUGAUAGAGAGCCUAGAGCCGUCUCAGUGCUCCAGGCGCUUGGCCCCUCCUUUCUACACAGUGGUCACCAGCAUCCUCCCUGGCGUCUCCUUCAUGAGUGGGCACUCCACCCUCUGCCCGGCCACCUGGCCCCCUCCUGGGGAGGACAGUCAGGCCCACAAAGAAGCUCCCUCUUUUUUUUUCUUUUCCCCUGCUCUGUUGUCCAGGCUGGAGUGCAGUGGCGCCAUCUCGGUUCACUGCAAGCUCCGCCUCCCGGCUUCACGCCAUUCUCCUGCCUCAGCCUCCCUAGGAGCUGGGACUACAGGCGCCUGCCACCACGCCCGGCUAAUUUUUAUUUUUAUUUUUAGUAGAGACAGGGUUUCAACGUGUUAGCCAGGAUGGUCUCAGUCUCCAGACCCUGUGAUCCGCCCGCCUCGGCCUCCCAAAGUGUUGGGAUUACAGGUGUGAGCCACCGUGCCUGGCCGAGGCUCCUUCUUUUAUGAGGAGCGGGAAGGCCUCCUGCACCCUGGAGACCGUGUGGGAAGACAAGCACAAGUAUGAGGAGGCCGAGCGGCGCUUCUACGAACACGAGGCCACACAGGCGGCCGCCUCCGCCCAGCAGCUGCCAGCCGAGGGGCCAGCCAUGAAUGGGCCCGGCCAGGACGACCCUGAGGACGCUGAUGAGGCGGAAGCCCCUGACGGCGGCAGCAGGCGUGAUCCCAGGAAGAGCCAGGACAGCAGGAAGCCCCUGCAGAAAAAGAGGAAGCGCUCCCCCAAGAGCGGGCUCGGCCCCGCGGACCUGGCCCUCCUGGGCCUCUCGGCCGAACGCGUGUGGCUGGACAAGUCACUUUUCGACCAGGCAGAGAGCUCCUACCGCCAGAAGCUGGCAGAUGUGGCUGCCCAGGCAGCCUGGCCUCCUGCCUUGGCCCCUUGGGGUCUCUGCACCCAUGGAAACCAGGUGGCCUGCCACCACGUGACCUGGGGGAUCUGGGUCAACAAGUCCUCCUUCGACCAGGCUGAGCGGGCCUUCGUGGAGUGGUCUCAGGCCCUGUUGCUGGCCCCCGACGGCAGCCGCAGGCAGGGGACUCCCAACACAGGCCAGCAGGUGGCCGUCCCCGACCUGGCCCACCAGCCCAGCCCACCGGUCAAUGGCCAGCCCCCGCUGGGCAGCCUGCAGGCACUGGUUCGGGAGGUGUGGCUGGAGAAGCCCCGGUAUGAUGCAGCCGAGAGGGGCUUCUACGAGGCCCUGUUUGACGGCCAUCCCCCAGGGAAGGUGCGCCUGCAAGAGCGAGCCGGCCUGGCCGAGGGUGCCCGGCGGGGCCGCAGAGACCGGCGGGGCCGCAACAUCUUAGGGAACAAGCGGGCCGGGCUGCGACGGGCCGAUGGGGAGGCCCCCUCUGCCUUGCCCUACUGUUACUUCCUGCAGAAGGAUGCAGAGGCCCCCUGGCUCAGCAAGCCUGCCUACGACAGCGCCGAGUGCCGCCACCACGCUGCCGAGGCCCUGCGGGUGGCCUGGUGCCUCGAAGCUGCCUCCCUGUCUCACCGACCCGGUCCUCGGUCUGGCCUGUCCGUGUCCAGCCUGAGACCCAACAGAAAAAUGGCUACAAACUUCCUAGCACAUGAGAAGAUCUGGUUCGACAAGUUCAAAUAUGACGACGCAGAAAGGAGAUUCUACGAGCAGAUGAACGGGCCUGUGGCAGGUGCCUCCCGCCAGGAGAACGGCGCCAGCGUGAUCCUCCGUGACAUUGCGAGAGCCAGAGAGAACAUCCAGAAAUCCCUGGCUGGAAGCUCAGGCCCCGGGGCCUCCAGCGGCACCAGCGGAGACCACGGUGAGCUCGUCGUCCGGAUUGCCAGUCUGGAAGUGGAGAACCAGAGUCUGCGUGGCGUGGUACAGGAGCUGCAGCAGGCCAUCUCCAAGCUGGAGGCCCGGCUGAACGUGCUGGAGAAGAGCUCGCCUGGCCACCGGGCCACGGCCCCACAGACCCAGCACGUAUCUCCCAUGCGCCAAGUGGAGCCCCCAGCCAAGAAGCCAGCCACACCAGCAGAGGAUGACGAGGAUGAUGACAUUGACCUGUUUGGCAGUGACAAUGAGGAGGAGGACAAGGAGGCGGCACAGCUGCGGGAGGAGCGGCUACGGCAGUACGCGGAGAAGAAGGCCAAGAAGCCUGCACUGGUGGCCAAGUCCUCCAUCCUGCUGGAUGUCAAGCCUUGGGAUGAUGAGACGGACAUGGCCCAGCUGGAGGCCUGUGUGCGCUCUAUCCAGCUGGACGGGCUGGUCUGGGGGGCUUCCAAGCUGGUGCCCGUGGGCUACGGUAUCCGGAAGCUACAGAUUCAGUGUGUGGUGGAGGACGACAAGGUGGGGACAGACUUGCUGGAGGAGGAGAUCACCAAGUUUGAGGAGCACGUGCAGAGUGUCGAUAUCGCAGCUUUCAACAAGAUCUGAAGCCUGAGUGUGUGUACGUGCGCGCGUGCGUGAGGCCCUGCCACGAUUAAAGACUGAGACCGGC